GGAGAGCGCGCGUGCGCCGUCACGAGCUCGGCGCUGCCGGGGCCGCGGUGUGGAAGCGAGUAUUCGACCGCCGUGCGGGCCGCGGGGAUGUUCCGAAAGGCCCGGCGGGUGAACGUGCGCAAGCGGAACGACUCCGAAGAGGAAGAGCGGGAACGCGAUGAGGAGCAGGAGCCGCCGCCGUUGUUGCCGCCGCCGGGCACGGGCGAAGAGGCGGGCCCCGGUGGCGGCGACAGGGCCCCUGGCGGGGAGUCGCUGCUGGGCCCGGGGCCGUCGCCGCCUUCCGCGCUGACCCCGGGCCUCGGGGCUGAGGCCGGGGGCGGCUUCCCCGGCGGCGCGGAGCCCGGCAACGGGCUGAAGCCGCGCAAGAGGCCUCGCGAGAACAAAGAGGUGCCCCGGGCCAGCCUGCUCAGCUUCCAGGACGAGGAGGAAGAAAAUGAAGAAGUUUUCAAAGUGAAGAAAUCAAGUUAUAGCAAAAAGAUAGUAAAAUUGCUCAAGAAGGAAUAUAAAGAAGAUCUUGAAAAAUCGAAGAUUAAGACAGAACUCAACUCAUCAGCUGAAAGUGAACAACCUUUGGACAAAACAGGACAUGUUAAGGAUACAAAUCAAGAAGAUGGAGUUAUCAUCAGUGAACAUGGUGAAGAUGAAAUGGAUAUGGAAAGUGAAAAAGAGGAAGAAAAGCCAAAGACUGGUGGAGCUUUUUCAAAUGCUUUAUCUUCAUUGAAUGUUCUUCGUCCAGGAGAAAUUCCAGAUGCAGCUUUUAUACAUGCUGCAAGGAAAAAGCGCCAAAUGGCCCGAGAAUUGGGAGAUUUCACUCCUCAUGAUAAUGAGCCUGGUAAAGGCCGCCUUGUUAGAGAAGAUGAGAAUGAUGCCAGUGAUGAUGAAGAUGACGAUGAGAAACGCCGGAUAGUUUUUUCUGUGAAAGAAAAGUCACAAAGACAAAAAAUUGCUGAGGAAAUAGGAAUUGAGGGGAGUGAUGAUGAUGCUUUAGUAACUGGAGAACAGGAUGAAGAGCUCAGCCGAUGGGAACAGGAGCAGAUAAGGAAAGGAAUUAAUAUCCCUCAGGUUCAAGCCAGUCAACCCGCAGAAGUGAAUAUGUACUACCAGAACACUUACCAGACAAUGCCUUACGGCUCAUCCUAUGGCAUUCCUUAUAGUUAUACGGCCUAUGGAUCAUCAGAUGCCAAAUCUCAAAAAACAGAUAAUACAGUCCCUUUCAAAACUCCCAGUAAUGAGAUGACUCCCGUUACUAUUGAUUUGGUAAAGAAACAGCUUAAAGACAGGUUGGACUCCAUGAAAGAAUUGCACAAAACAAAUCGACAGCAGCAUGAGAAACAUCUGCAAAGCCGAGUGGACUCUACCAGGGCUAUUGAAAGAUUAGAAGGGUCUUCUGGGGGUAUUGGUGAACGGUAUAAAUUUUUGCAAGAAAUGCGAGGGUAUGUCCAAGACUUGCUUGAGUGUUUCAGUGAAAAGGUGCCACUGAUUAAUGAACUUGAAUCAGCAAUACAUCAGCUGUACAAACAGCGAGCUUCCCGCCUUGUCCAAAGACGACAAGAUGAUAUUAAAGAUGAAUCUUCGGAGUUUUCAAGCCAUUCAAACAAAGCUCUGAUGGCACCAAAUCUUGACUCCUUUGGACGCGAUCGGGCACUGUAUCAAGAGCAUGCAAAACGUCGCAUUGCAGAGCGGGAGGCCAGGAGGACUCGUCGUAGACAAGCCAGAGAACAAACCGGUAAGAUGGCAGAUCACCUUGAAGGCCUUUCCAGUGAUGAUGAAGAAACUUCUACAGAUAUUACUAAUUUCAAUCUGGAAAAAGAUCGAAUUUCAAAAGAAUCCGGCAAAGUUUUUGAAGAUGUCCUUGAAAGUUUCUAUUCAAUUGACUGUAUUAAAUCACAGUUUGAAGCAUGGCGUUCAAAAUACUACACAUCCUACAAAGAUGCUUACAUUGGCCUUUGUUUGCCAAAAUUAUUCAACCCCCUCAUACGACUUCAGCUCCUCACUUGGACUCCUCUUGAGCCAGCUGAAAUUAUAUGCAGUAACACUGGGAUAUGAACAUGAAUAGUAAGAACUUGGUCCUUUGAUCCUAGAGGAACUCAGAACCAGAUGGGAAAGCACAAUGAGGCAGGUGUGAAAUGAGGACAUGACCCAAGUCAGUUGUCAUGGUGAGAAAAAUUGAUAGGCCAGGCAUGGUGGCUCAUGCUUGUAAUCCCAACAGUUUGGGAGGCCAAGGCGGGAGGAUUGUUUGAGCUCAGGAGUUCAAGACCAGCCUGGGCAACAUAGCAAGACCUUGUCUCUACUUAAAAAAAAAAAAAAAAAAUUAGCUGUGGUGGCAUGUGCUCAUAUUCCUAGCUACUUCGGGGGCUGAGGCAGGAUUGCUUGAGCCCGGGAGAUCAAGGCUGUAAUGAGCUAUGAUUGUGCCACUGCACUGCAGCCUGGGUGAUAGAACAAGACCUGCCACAAGAAAAAAAAAAAAAGAUAAGGAGGUGGAAUCAAGAGGACCUAUUGGCCUGUCAUAUAAGGGAGGGGGCUAGAAUUGACUCUGGAGGUCUAGUGGUGAUGUUUACAAUGUGGUUUUAGAAGUUACCAACGUGGGUGAAGCUGUAGACAUGGUUGAGAUUGGCUAGGUUGAAUUUGUGAACUAUAAGGAAAAGGGAGCUGAGGUUGAUGCCAUGGAAACACAACUGAAAAAAAUGUGAGCUCUGAGAAGCAUUCAGCUCACAGCUCCUAUUUCCUGUGUGCUCUUGGCCAGACCUUCUGAAGUUUUGCUGUGUGCAUGAGUGUCUUGGUAGAUAGCAAAGGCCCAAGACUGUAUUUUGGAGUUAUUUUUCUGUGUCCCCCACUCCUCUGCCCCACAGUUUCCAGCUGUGUCAGCCUUCCUGAGCUCCACCCUCUGUCUCCUCCACUCAGCAAAACUGCUCUGCUGUCCUGAACUAGCAUCUCACCUCAUUUGAUUCCUUUCUUUAAAGGGUCAUAGUCUUGUGCUGCCUAUGGUCCAUUGUAUUUUGUCCAGUUCUUUUUUAUUUUCUUUGGCUUUUAAGUUCCAGGGUACAUGUGCAGAUUUGUUACAUAGGUAAACAUGUGACAUGGUGGUUUACAGCACAGAUCAACCCAUCACCUUGGUAGGAAGCCUAGCAUCCAGUAGCUGUUGUUGCUCUCCCUCCCCCAAGUCCCCACCCCCACCCCCCAACAGGCCUCAGUGUGUGUUUUUCCCCAGUAUGUGUCCAUAUAUUCUCAUUGUUCAGCUCCCACUUGCGAGAACAUGUGGUGCUUGGGUUUCUGUUCCUGCGUUAGUUUGCUGAGGAUAAUGGCUUCUAGCUCCAUCCAUGUCCCUGCAAAGGACAUGACCUCGUUCCUUUUUAUGGCUGCAUAGUAUUCCAUGGUGUAUAUGUAUAACAUUUUCUUUAUCCAGUCUAUAAUUGAUGGGCAUUUGGGUUGAUUCCAUGUCUUUGCUAUUGUGAAUAGUGCUGCAGUGAACAUACAUAUGCAUGUAGCUUUAUAAUAGAAUGAUUUAUAUUUCUGUAGGUAUAUACCCAGUAAUGGGAUUGCUGGGUCAAAUGGCAUUUCUGCUUCUAGAUCUGUGAGGAAUUGGCACACUGUCUUCCUUACACUCCCACCAAUAGUGUAAAAGUGUUCCUUUUUCUCUGAAACCUUACCAGCAUCUUUUGUUUCUGGACUUUUAAAUAAUUCCCAUUCUGAUUGGCAUGGGAUGGUAUCUCAUUGUGGUUUAGAUUUGCAUUUCUCCAAUCAUCGGUGAUGUUGAGCUUUUUUUCAUGUUUGUUGGCUACAUGAAUGUCUUCUUUUGAGAAGUAUCUGUUCAUGUCCUUUGCCCACUUUUAAUGGGGUUGUUUUUUUCCUAUAAAGUUUCCUGUAGACUCUGGAUAUUAGACCUUUGUCAGAUGGAUAGAUUGCAAGAAUUUUCUCCCAUUCUGUAGGUUGUCUGUUCACUCUGAUAAUAGUUUCUUUUGCUGCGUAGAAGCUCUUUAGUUGAAUUAGAUACCAUUUGUCAAUUUUUGCUUUUGUUGCAGUUGCUUUUGGUGUUUUUGUCGUGAAAUCUUUGCCCAUGCCGAUGUCUUGAAUGGUAUUGCCUAGAUUUUCUUCUAGGAUUUUUAUAGUUUUGGGGUUUACAUUUAAGUCUUUAAUCCAUCUUGACUUAACUUUUGUAUAUGGUGUAAGGAAGGAGCCCAGUUUCAAUUUUCUGUAUAUGGCUAGCCAAUUCUCCCAACACCAUUUAUUAAACAGGGAAUCUUUUCCCCAUUGCUUGUUCGUGUCAGGUUUGUCGGAGAUCAGAUGGUUGUAGGUGUGCGGUCUUAUUGCUGAGUUCUCUAUUCUGUUCCAUUGGUCUAUGUGUCUGUUUUUGUAUCAGUACCAUGCUGUUUUGGUUACUGUGGCCUUAUAGUUUGAAGUCUGGUAGCAUGAUAUCUCCAGCCGUCCAGUUUUUAGUUGUUUGCAACCAAAGGUUAAAUCCAGUUCUUGUUUCUCUUAUCAUAGCUGGAAGCAGAAAUAGCCACUAUUUUAGUAUUUGGGUAACCUUUUAAAUGUCU